ACUGUCUCAUGGCACCUCUUGUCACCACUUGAUUUUCCUGUGUGUGAUCUUCUCCCCCAGACACACAGUUUCUGGAGGGCAGGGACUGGCUCCUAUUUGAUUCCCCAAGGCUGCUCCAGGCAAGGUCUGGUGUCCCAUAAGUGCUUGUGGACUGACUGGUAGCUGGAAGGAUUGAAAAGGCCACCUGUGUUGAGAGGAGGAGGUAGAAACUAAAGAAUAUCCAGCUUCUUUCCUUUUUCCCAGCCCACAAGGUCACAAGGAAAGAGGUGGGGACAUACCCAAGUCCGGACAGAGGAAAAAUGUGGGCAGGGCCUCUGCAGAGGGGCAGAGGGCUCAGGAGGGCAGAUACCAGCUGGAUAACGAGUGGGAAUGGGUGGGAGAAAGUUUCAGAGAAAAGGUAGAGAAAGGAGGAGGGACCAUCUUAUCUAGUUUAUCAUUUUACAGGUGAGGAGGCCAAGACCACGUUCUAGGGCUUUAUUGAUUAUAAUCAGACCCUCAAGUGCAAAGUAGGGUUUAUUGAAAGUAUUCAGGGAAGGAGUUCACUGCAACUCAUUGGUAGGAAAUGUAGCCUCGAGGGGCCUUUUCAGCUCAAGUGCUUCCCCUGAUUACCAGUGUUUCUGUGUCUCUAAAUUCACAUUUAUCUAUAAUUCAAAUACUGAGUACCUUCCAUGGGGUAGCACUGUACUGGGAAUGAAAUUGUAAGCAAAAGCAGAGGUCACCUUAGCCCAGUGGGGAGGGGUGGAUUUUUCUUCUCAUCUGUCUUCCCUGCGGCCUAUGGGUGGGGUAGACCAAGCCAGAAUGGGAAGCCAAAGGGACAAGUGCACAGUCCAGAGAGGGUCAGUGACUUGUUCAAAGUCACACAAGGCUGGAACUUGGGUCCUGCAGUGCUGGUUUCAGGGCUCUUCCUGUGCUCAAACAUGUUCCUCAUUCAUCUUUACUUACUUUUUGAUGCAGGGAGUGGAGGGUGGGGUGGCCUGAGACCCCUAUGGCGGCAAAGGGAGGUCAGAGAGUGUGAUGUGGGUGUUUAUGGAGAUGCACUUGAGUGCAGGACUGGGGCACGGGCUGGGACCAGGGCUAAGGGUGACAGCUAGGCCUACCGGAGGGGUACUGGAUGGAGGAGAGAAUUGUUCACAAGGAAGCCACAGGCUGAAAACACUGAGAAACAGCCUCCAGGGGCCAGCUGCAGACUUCAGUUUCCAAUUCCUGAAUUCACCUCUUCUACAGUAAUGCCAGCCCACUGGCCUGACUGCCAGGGCCGAAUGCCCAGGACCUAGACUUUGGUCUGCACAGUCAGAGGAAAGAGAGCAGGGCAGCAGUGUUGAGUGGAGUGACUAACUCUGGAUUAGCAGUGAUCCUGGGCUCUCAGCCCAGCUCGGCCAUUACAGGCAGUAUCUUCACCUGUCAGGCUCUGGUUUACUCACUGGAUGCAAAAUGAAGAAGAUGGACAAGUUGAAGAAACGUCACAGGAGCCCAAGAGGCUGGCCAGAGAGCCCAGGACUCAGUUCCUCUGUGGGAAGGCACACACACUCUUUGGUCAAGAAACUUGGUCAGGAGGUCAGAAACAUGGGCCCUGCCCGAGCAGCAAGUCACCAUGACCCAGGCCAACCUGAGGACAAAGGCCUCAACUAUUCCUUGAACCAUGCUGAUAAUCAGGACAUUCCGAAGAAACAAGUGAUGUGGAUUUCAGUGACGGCCUACCUCCAGAAGACUUCCUUCAGCCUGAUGUCUUCCUCAAGACCAGCCAACCCCGAACCAUGAGCUGAUGGGGCCACGUGCAUUUCACAGGUUACUGACUGGGUGGGCUGAAUGAUGGCCCCCAAAGACAGCCAGGUCCUAACCCCUGGAACCUGUGAAUAUUACCCUACAUGGCAAAACGGACUUUGCUGGUGUGACUGAAAGCCCUUGAGUGGGGAGAUUAUCCCGGAUUAUUCAGAUGGAUCUUAAAUGUAAUCACAAGGGUCCUUCUAAAAGAGAGGCAGAGGAAGAUUUUACUACAGAAGACAAACAAAGCCAUAUGACAAAGGAAGCAGACAGAGAGAGAGAUUUGGAAAUGCUAUGCUGCUGGCUUUGAAGAUGGGUAAGAGGCCAAGAGCCAAAGAAUGCAAACACUGCAGCUCUGGAUGCUAGAAAGGGCAAGGAAAUGUAGAGCCCCUGCAGGCUCUGCUUACCCCUUAAUUUUGGCCCAGUGAAACUGAUUUCAGAUUUCUGAUCUGCAGAACUGAAAGAGAAUAAAUGUGUGUUGCUUUCAGCCACCAAGUUUGUGGCAAUUUGUUACAGCAGCCACAGGACGCUAAUACAUGACCCUUUACUCUCUGACUCUUGUACUCAGCACUUGGGAUCAAACAGUGAACCCGAUAAACCUCUACACCUCCCAGGGAAAUUGACCAUCUCUCUGUCUCUGGAUUUUAAAAAGGAACAGCCACGUAGACAUUUUAUCAAAGAUAUAUGAAUGGUCAAUAAACACAUGAAAAGAAAAUGCACAAAAUCAUUAGCAUUAGGGCAAUGAAAAUUAAAACCACAAUGAGAUACCACUUCAUACUCACUAGGAUGGCUAUAAUAAAAGACAAUAACAAAUGUCAAAA